GAAAUCCAACCCGGUCACCUACCCGCGCGACUGUGUCCACGGAUGGCACGAAAGCCAAGCGAGUCCCCCUGCCGAGCUACUCGCGUCCGCCUCCUCCCAAGCUGAGCUCUGCUCCGCCCACCUGAGUCCUUCGCCAGUUAGGAGGAAACACAGCCGCUUAAUGAACUGCUGCAUCGGGCUGGGAGAGAAAGCUCGCGGGUCCCACCGGGCCUCCUACCCAAGUCUCAGCGCGCUUUUCACCGAGGCCUCAAUUCUGGGAUUUGGCAGCUUUGCUGUGAAAGCCCAAUGGACAGAGGACUGCAGAAAAUCAACCUAUCCUCCUUCAGGACCAACGUACAGAGGUGCAGUUCCAUGGUACACCAUAAAUCUUGACUUACCACCCUACAAAAGAUGGCAUGAAUUGAUGCUUGACAAGGCACCAGUGCUAAAGGUUAUAGUGAAUUCUCUGAAGAAUAUGAUAAAUACAUUCGUGCCAAGUGGAAAAAUUAUGCAGGUGGUGGAUGAAAAAUUGCCUGGCCUACUUGGCAACUUUCCUGGCCCUUUUGAAGAGGAAAUGAAGGGUAUUGCCGCUGUUACUGAUAUACCUUUAGGAGAGAUUAUUUCAUUCAAUAUUUUUUAUGAAUUAUUUACCAUUUGUACUUCAAUAGUAGCAGAAGACAAAAAAGGUCAUCUAAUACAUGGGAGAAACAUGGAUUUUGGAGUAUUUCUUGGGUGGAACAUAAAUAAUGAUACCUGGGUCAUAACUGAGCAACUAAAACCUUUAACAGUGAAUUUGGAUUUCCAAAGAAACAACAAAACUGUCUUCAAGGCUUCAAGCUUUGCUGGCUAUGUGGGCAUGUUAACAGGAUUCAAACCAGGACUGUUCAGUCUUACACUGAAUGAACGUUUCAGUAUAAAUGGUGGUUAUCUGGGUAUUCUAGAAUGGAUUCUGGGAAAGAAAGAUGUCAUGUGGAUAGGGUUCCUCACUAGAACAGUUCUGGAAAAUAGCACAAGUUAUGAAGAAGCCAAGAAUUUAUUGACCAAGACCAAGAUAUUGGCCCCAGCCUACUUUAUCCUGGGAGGCAACCAGUCUGGGGAAGGUUGUGUGAUUACACGAGACAGAAAGGAAUCAUUGGAUGUAUAUGAACUCGAUGCUAAGCAGGGUAGAUGGUAUGUGGUACAAACAAAUUAUGACCGUUGGAAACAUCCCUUCUUCCUUGAUGAUCGCAGAACGCCUGCAAAGAUGUGUCUGAACCGCACCAGCCAAGAGAAUAUCUCAUUUGAAACCAUGUAUGAUGUCCUGUCAACAAAACCUGUCCUCAACAAGCUGACCGUAUACACAACCUUGAUAGAUGUUACCAAAGGUCAAUUCGAAACUUACCUGCGGGACUGCCCUGACCCUUGUAUAGGUUGGUGAGCACACGUCUGGCCUACAGAAUGCGGCCUCUGAGACAUGAAGACACCAUCUCCAUGUGACCGAACACUGCAGCUGUCUGACCUUCCAAAGACUAAGACUCGCGGCAGGUUCUCUUUGAGUCAAUAGCUUGUCUUCGUCCAUCUGUUGACAAAUGACAGAUCUUUUUUUUUUCCCCCUAUCAGUUGAUUUUUCUUAUUUACAGAUAACUUCUUUAGGGGAAGUAAAACAGUCAUCUAGAAUUCACUGAGUUUUGUUUCACUUUGACAUUUGGGGAUCUGGUGGGCAGUCGAACCAUGGUGAACUCCACCUCCGUGGAAUAAAUGGAGAUUCAGCGUGGGUGUUGAAUCCAGCACGUCUGUGUGAGUAACGGGACAGUAAACACUCCACAUUCUUCAGUUUUUCACUUCUACCUACAUAUUUGUAUGUUUUUCUGUAUAACAGCCUUUUCCUUCUGGUUCUAACUGCUGUUAAAAUUAAUAUAUCAUUAUCUUUGCUGUUAUUGACAGCGAUAUAAUUUUAUUACAUAUGAUUAGAGGGAUGAGACAGACAUUCACCUGUAUAUUUCUUUUAAUGGGCACAAAAUGGGCCCUUGCCUCUAAAUAGCACUUUUUGGGGUUCAAGAAGUAAUCAGUAUGCAAAGCAAUCUUUUAUACAAUAAUUGAAGUGUUCCCUUUUUCAUAAUUACUCUACUUCCCAGUAACCCUAAGGAAGUUGCUAACUUAAAAAACUGCAUCCCACGUUCUGUUAAUUUAGUAAAUAAACAAGUCAAAGACUUGUGGAAAAUAGGAAGUGAACCCAUAUUUUAAAUUCUCAUAAGUAGCAUUCAUGUAAUAAACAGGUUUUUAGUUUGUUCUUCAGAUUGAUAGGGAGUUUUAAAGAAAUUUUAGUAGUUACUAAAAUUAUGUUACUGUAUUUUUCAGAAAUCAAACUGCUUAUGAAAAGUACUAAUAGAACUUGUUAACCUUUCUAACCUUCACGAUUAACUGUGAAAUGUACGUCAUUUGUGCAAGACCGUUUGUCCACUUCAUUUUGUAUAAUCACAGUUGUGUUCCUGACACUCAAUAAACAGUCACUGGAAAGAGUGCCAGUCAGCAGUCAUGCACGCUGAUUGGGUGUGUACAUCUGUGUUGGUUUGGAGGAGGGGGGUUAUUAUCAAGAAAUACAAGCUGAACAUCGUAUCUGAAUUAAAUAACAAGGGUUAUGUAAGUGGGUUAUUAAAUAUGACUAAACGGUCACAAUCUUACUCUUACAUGACUGAUACCACCUCUUAACCAGAUACUAUCAACCCAAUUUGCAGGUGUUUAAAGGCAGUUUUUCCCCCAGAUAGGUGGUGCUUCCACAAAACUUUAGUGAUUCCAAGAUUACUUUAGUGAAACGAGGAAUUAUAAGAGGAUUUACAUUAAAAUAGGAUUUAAUUAAUGAAAAAAAAACUUUACUCAGAUUUUCUACCUCUUACAUAAAUGAAGUCAGGUCAACUUGAUGUAUUUUUUUGUUAAUGUAAUAACCUUUGAUAUGCCUGAUAGUAAAGAGGUGAGAUGCUAA